AUGACUCCACACCCCCCACAUCUCCAAGUCUCAGAAACCAUCGUUCUGAGAACCCCAAGGAGGACACCCUUUCCCGGGUCUUCUGCAGCGCCGAGCCCCGGCAGGCCUCCCCGGCGCUCGCCUGCUGCGAGACCUUCCUGCCGCCCCGAGGAGCACGAGACCCCAGCCGCCUGCAGAUCACCCACAUUUGCGGAGGGUGGCAGCAGGGGCUUGGCUGGAAGGCUGAGCCCUGGGAGCGCGUGGACUCCGCCCUACCGCCCGGCGAUUGGCUCGCGGGGCUGGGGGCGGAGACCGAGUCCGCGCUGUAUAAAUAUUCAUGAGCCGGCAGCGCGGCGCGAGCGGGGCUGGAGCCGGGAAGUUGGGCUAAGGGCGCUGCUCCCGCCGAGGAGGAGGCGGCGGCUGGGCGCGGGCCGCGCCACUCAGGUGUCCGCUCCGCCUUCCGGUCUGGAUUUGCUCCUGGGUGUCCAGCAGGAAGGAGACUGUGUGCACCUCGCCCGACUGCGGCCGGAGCGCGGCGCUGACUUUUCCAGGCGGCGGGGGUCCGUCUGUCCCGGCGGCGGACGGACGAAGGACGGACGCCGGAGAAAGAGGGCGGCGGCCUGGGCCGAGGCGGGUCCCCAACUCCGGCGGCGGCGGCGGCGGCUUGGCCUUGGGGGCGGGCAUGAGCCCCCGGGGGCCGAGUGGUGGCCGCCAGGGCUGACCCGGCGCGGCAAGCGGCCCGGCCCAGCCAUCUUGACUGCGCACCGCGGCCCCAGAGGAAACUUGCGGCGCCUCCGCCCUCUCUGUCCGGCGGAGUCACCGCCGCCCGGCGCGGCGGGGAGAAGUGGUCGGGCGCGCGGAGAGGAGGCGAGCGAGCGCGGGACGAUGAGCCGAGGCCCGGCCGCUCUGCGCCGCGAGGGCUGA